ACAGUUGAAGAAGCGACCGAGGGACUGGGAGUCGUUAGUGAGGUGAGUUCGAGGCGGUGCAGGAAGAGUGUUGCUGGGAUCGCUUUCCUGCGGGCUAGAGGCCUGGGGUCUUGAGGGAGACUGGGGCAAGAUUUUGGAUUCCCGAUUCCCUGUCAAUCAUUAUUAAUACAGCUGUCCGGGCGCCCCAAGUUUGAAGCUGAACUACACUCUGCUGGAGGUGGCCAACCGUCCAUCGGGCAGUUCUCUCUCUCUUUGUCUCUCUCUCUCACUAUAAACUCAGUCAAGUGGUAGCUAGCAUCGGCCAGUUCUCCUGAGAGUUACAGUUCUGCUGUAGAUGAUGGCUAUUUGCUGGUGGUCCCAAGGGAAGGAGUGGACUGGGAUUGCUGGGGGUCUAAGGAGUGGGAGUUGAGGAGGGAGAACUCCUUUCCUGGCCUCAGUUUCUCAGACUGUGGUGGGACGGCGGGCGAUACUAGAUUGUGCAGUCAUCCAUCGCCACCUUCUCUUCACCUUUUUGACAGCCCCUUCCCUUUCGGGGUUGGUGCAGGGAUUCACGUUUUCUUGUGUGGAGCUUCGGGGUCAGGCAGUCAUGGAUUCCCAUUCUGAUUGUGCUGCUAAUUCUGUGAACUUGGGGCUUGAACGGUCCUUGAGGCAGUUUGAUGUUAAUGUUUUCUUACGAAAAUGUUCAAACUUAUAUAAAAGUGAGAGAAGAAUACAGGAAUUCCUGUCACCCAAAUCACCAAUGAUUAUUUUUGCCAUACUUGCUGUAUUUUUUUAAACUUAAAGAGAUUAAAACAAAUCGUAGGCAUCAUGACACUUAAGGAUUGUCAAAAGACAAAAUUGCAACACAUUUAGUGAGAAGAUCUUAAUUGGCAUUUAUUCGUGAAUCUACAAUCAAACAACAUCUAAUUAUGGAAAAUAGCGUGAGUGUUCCGAUGAGCUGAGCAGAGGUUGUUUUCAGAGACAAAGGGCUGAGAAAAUCAGAAACGGAAAACAAAAAGCUAGUUGAUUAAAUUGAUUAACUUGAUUAAAUUUCUAAGUUAAAGGUUAAAGUAGAGGGGACUUCCUUUAUCAGGUGGGCUAAAACUGGGUUGUUUGGGGAUUUGGCUAUUAUCUCUCUCCUGAUAUCUCAGAAGAUCAGAUAUCAACUUAGUUUUGGCUUGGAAGCAUGGAACUUUAGCAUGAGUGUCUCCAUUUUGGUUUGGUCUGUUGAACCUAGUGCAGGAGCUCAAUCCAAACCAAUGACCUUCUAUAAAUUUUAUCUAACAGGGUGCGUGUGUAAAAACCAGAAACAUUGCUGAUAUGACCACAAUACCAUCAUCACACUUUAAAAGAACAACCGUAAUUCUAGACUACUAUCCAUUACGUGGUGCAGAGUCAAGUCCAGUGUAACUGUGGGUUUGUUGGAAUCAGGAUAUAGAUGACGCGGCAUGGCAAGAACUGCACCGCAGGGGCCGUCUACACCUACCACGAGAAGAAGAAGGACACAGCGGCCUCGGGCUAUGGGACCCAGAACAUUCGACUGAGCCGGGAUGCCGUGAAGGACUUCGACUGCUGUUGUCUCUCCCUGCAGCCUUGCCACGAUCCUGUUGUCACCCCAGAUGGCUACCUGUAUGAGCGUGAGGCCAUCCUGGAGUACAUUCUGCACCAGAAGAAGGAGAUUGCCCGGCAGAUGAAGGCCUACGAGAAGCAGCGGGGCACCCGGCGCGAGGAGCAGAAGGAGCUUCAGCGGGCGGCCUCGCAGGACCAUGUGCGGGGCUUCCUGGAGAAGGAGUCGGCUAUCGUGAGCCGGCCCCUCAACCCUUUCACAGCCAAGGCCCUCUCGGGCACCAGCCCAGGUGACUCAGAUGAUGUCCAACCUGGGCCCAGUGUGGGUCCUCCAAGUAAGGACAAGGACAAAGUGCUGCCCAGCUUCUGGAUCCCGUCGCUGACGCCCGAAGCCAAGGCCACCAAGCUGGAGAAGCCGUCCCGCACGGUGACCUGCCCCAUGUCAGGGAAGCCCCUGCGCAUGUCGGACCUGACGCCCGUGCACUUCACACCGCUAGACAGCUCCGUGGACCGCGUGGGGCUCAUCACCCGCAGCGAGCGCUACGUGUGUGCCGUGACCCGCGACAGCCUGAGCAACGCCACCCCCUGCGCUGUGCUGCGGCCCUCUGGGGCUGUGGUCACCCUCGAAUGCGUGGAGAAGCUGAUUCGGAAGGACAUGGUGGACCCUGUGACUGGAGACAAACUCACAGACCGCGACAUCAUCGUGCUGCAGCGGGGCGGUACCGGCUUCGCGGGCUCCGGAGUGAAGCUGCAAGCGGAGAAAUCACGGCCGGUGAUGCAGGCCUGAGUGUGUGCGGGAGACCAAAUAAACCGGCUUGGGUGCGCAACGACGUGGCGCCUUCAUUCGCGGCGUGGGCGCCCCGGGGACAGGGCAGGCGAGGAUGCAGGGCCGUGCAAACAGUGCUCCUACAGCGCACGCUGGAGUUUGAAAGAGCGGGCUAAGCAUAUUGAAUGUGGUCUCACAUUAAGAACAAAAUCUGGCCAGGCACGGUGGCUCACGCCUGUAAUCCCAGCACUUUCGGAGGCCGAGGCUAGCGUAUCACUUGAGGUCAGGAGUUCGAGACCAGCCU